AGUCUCGUGGAGAGAUUGAAGAUGGCGGCUUCUCAGGCGGUGGAGGAAAUGCGGAGCCGCGUGGUUCUGGGGGAGUUUGGGGUUCGCAAUGUCCAUACUACUGACUUUCCCGGUAACUAUUCCGGUUAUGAUGAUGCCUGGGACCAGGACCGCUUCGAGAAGAAUUUCCGUGUGGAUGUAGUACACAUGGAUGAAAACUCACUGGAGUUUGACAUGGUGGGAAUUGACGCAGCCAUUGCCAAUGCUUUUCGACGAAUUCUGCUAGCUGAGGUGCCAACUAUGGCUGUGGAGAAGGUCCUGGUGUACAAUAAUACAUCCAUUGUUCAGGAUGAGAUUCUUGCUCACCGUCUGGGGCUCAUUCCCAUUCAUGCUGAUCCCCGUCUUUUUGAGUAUCGGAACCAAGGAGAUGAAGAAGGCACAGAGAUAGAUACUCUACAGUUUCGUCUCCAGGUCAGAUGCACUCGGAACCCCCAUGCUGCUAAAGAUUCCUCUGACCCCAACGAACUGUACGUGAACCACAAAGUGUAUACCAGGCAUAUGACAUGGAUCCCCCUGGGGAACCAGGCUGAUCUCUUUCCAGAGGGCACUAUCCGACCAGUGCAUGAUGAUAUCCUCAUCGCUCAGCUGCGGCCUGGCCAAGAAAUUGACCUGCUCAUGCACUGUGUCAAGGGCAUUGGCAAAGAUCAUGCCAAGUUUUCACCAGUGGCAACAGCCAGUUACAGGCUCCUGCCAGACAUCACCCUGCUUGAGCCCGUGGAAGGGGAGGCAGCUGAGGAGUUGAGCAGGUGCUUCUCACCUGGUGUUAUUGAGGUGCAGGAAGUCCAAGGUAAAAAGGUGGCCAGAGUUGCCAACCCCCGGCUGGAUACCUUCAGCAGAGAAAUCUUCCGGAAUGAGAAGCUAAAGAAGGUUGUGAGGCUUGCCCGGGUUCGAGAUCAUUAUAUCUGUAAGAAAGAUUUGCUGGCUGCGGUGGCUCACACCUGUAAUCCCAGCACUUUGGGAGGCCAAGGCGAGUGGAUCACGGGGUCAAGAGAGCGAGACCAUCCUGGCUAACAUGGUGAAACCCCGUCUCUACUAAAAAAAAAAAAAAAAAAAAAAAAAAUUAGUCGGGCAUGGGGGCGAGCGCCUGUAGUCCCAGCUACUCGAGAAGCUAAGGCAAGAGAAUGGUGUGAACCUGGGAGGCGAAGCUUGCAGUGAGCCGAGAUCACGCCACUGCACUCCAGCCUGGGCAACAGAGCAAGACUCCGUCUCAAAAAAAAAAAAAAAGAAAAGAAAGAAAGAGAUUCAACUAUUAAUAAGGGUCUGAAUGAGAAUGAAGUGUUAAAACUGCUGCUUCUGGCUGGGUGUGGUGGCUCAGGCCUGUAAUUCUAGCACUUUGGAGGCUGAGGCAGGAGAAUUACUUGAGCCAGGAGUUUGAGACCACCCUGGGGAACAUAAUACAGACCCAUCUCUACAAAUAAUAAUAAAAACUAGCUGGGUGUGGUGGUGCGCAUCUGUGGUCCAGUCCAGGCUCUUCAGGAAGCUGAGGUGGGAGGAUCACUUGAGCCUGCACUGAGCUUUGAUGGCACCACUGCAUUCCUGCCUGGGUAACACUGAGACCCUGUCUCAAAAAAAAAAAAAAAAAAGUGCUUCUAAAAAUACAGAAAAGGGAUAAAAGUUUUAUCUUUCACAGCUGGGCAUGGUGGCUCACACCUGUAACCCCAGCACUUUGGGAGGCUGAGGCAGGCGGAUUACUUGAGGUCAGGAGUUUGAGACCAGCCUGGCCAACAUGGCGAAAACCUGUCUCUACUAAAAAUACAAAAAAAUUAGCUGGGCGUAGUAGCAUGCGCCUGUAAUCCCAGCUACUUGGGAGGCUGAGGCACAUGAAUCACUUGAACCCAGGAGGUGGAAGUUGCAGUAAGACAAGAUCAUGCCACUGCACUCCAGCCUGGGCAAUAGAGCAAAACUCUGUCUCAAAAAAUAGGAAUAAAAAUCAGCUGGGCGUGAUGGUGCACACCUGUAAUCACAGCUAGUUAGGAGGCUGAGGCACAAGAAUAGCUUGAACCUGAGAGGCAGAAGCUGUGAGCCGAGAUCAUACCACUGCACUCCAGCCUGUGCAACAGAGUGAGCAAGACUGUCUCAAAAAAAAAAAAAAGUUUUAUCUGUAAUAAUUCCGAGAAGGGGGAAGGUAAAAAUUUACCCCUAAGGAAAAGUUUAUGGCCAUCUGGACUGCCUUCAUGUUUUCCCUGCAAUCUGCCAGUGUUUUUAAUGACAUGAUACACUUAGAUACAUAAUCUCAUCUCUUCCUUCCAGUUCUGCCUCUUCCCUCUGGUUGCUGUGACCUGUUUUGUUUCUCUCUCUAAUUUUCUGACCUUUUGGGUUAUGUAGAGACUUUUGAAAGGAUAUGAAGCAUGGGUCUGAGUCGGUAGUCAGGAAUAUUGUUCAAGUUGACAAAGGCUGAGCUGAGAAGCUGGGUAGCAAGGUCCUCCACAGUAUAGAAGUCUUGCUGCAUGGAAGGGCCUGCCUUCCCUAGGAUAUGAAAACUGUAAAGGGGAAAAAAAGAGCAUUGAAAAUGACAAAUCCAACAUCUGUUACUGCCAGCCCUGUCCCAUGAAUUUCAUUUCUAGCCUACAAUAAGGUUUUUCAGCCAGAAGAGCAGUUGUAUUUACUUAAGAGAACUUAUAGAUACAGCAUCUUUUUAAAGACAGAUGUUGGUGGCCGAGAUCAGCAGUAGCUUUCAUUACUAUUUAAUGUGGACUUACAAUGGACGAUCUCAUUAGCUUGGCUGAUUAGUGUAGUGGUUAGUGAGGCCAAAGCCCAUGAGGGCCAGUUACCUCCCCAACCCACAACCAGUAUCCAGCCACCCGACUCCUAUGAGAAGUAUGCCGCAAGCAGUGUAGGGUCUAAGCAAUCCCCACCACUUUUAGCUUCGACUUGGGUUUCAUCAUUUUAUACACUAGAAACACAGACAAGUUGGGCAUGAAGCAGGCUGGGAUUGUGAGGCUCAUAUGACAAUUACAAAAAAAGCAAAUGCAGGAAAGCAGGCUUUCAUUUCUAUUUAACACUAGAAUGAUAAGUUUCCUAUCAAACUCUUGCCUCGCCUUACCUGUACACUAGAUGAAAAGUCCAACCCAUGGACAUUCCUAUACAAUACAUAUCGAGGAAGAAAAUAUGGAGAGGCAGCAUUGGUUCCUUACCAGUUUUCAUAGAGGGUAGAGAAGAAACGCUGCAUUCUUUCCAAGACGGUUUUGAAGACAGGAGAGUCAUUGAGUUCCAAGAGAGGUUGAGGUAAUCCUACAGGGAAAUACGGGUCAAGAACAUGAUGCUCCACUGUCAGGAGUCUCAAUUGGCCAACACUCUACAGCAGGAAGCUGUUGUUCAGGGGUGAAGAUGUGUGCAUGUCUGGUGCUGUACUGCAAAGCAGUUGGCUACGUGAUUUGCUGCACUCUUUUGGUAGGAGAAGGUGAAAGCUACUUAAGGACCCAGGACUUUAGACCCGGGUACUCUUUUAUCUGCUUUUUUUUUUCCCCCAGAUGGAACCUGUACCAAAAAAAGUGACAACUCAAAAGUAUUUUUCCAUAAAGCUCUGGGGAUGCUCCCACAAUUAAGUUAUGAAACCCCUUUUUUAAGCAAAAUCUUACACAAAACACUAAGAUGUGUAGCAGCUAAAAAUGAAACCCACUUACCUUAGUAUUAAAAACUGCCUUAAAAUAUCUAUAUUUUUAAGUGUAAUCAGAGGUUUUACAUUUCGAGUCCUAUAGUCAGAAGCUAUCUGUGGGAACUGUUUGUCCAUUCUAGUAUUUCUGGUUGGCCACUUAUUUCUAUAGCAGGAGUUCCUGACUUAACUUGAAUAAUGGCAUGGGGGUGUGUGGUAAGCAACACCUACUUUUUAUAUUAAUAGCUAUACAUUUCUUGGAAUUUCUACUUUUACUGGUGUCUGCAACAUAACCCUUAAAUGGAAUGGUGUCAAAGGAAAAGAUUCAGGACUAUCUAGGCUGAAACAGACAGACAUGAGUUCUGGAAAGGCAAAUUAACAUCCUUCCUUUGGCUAACUUCACAGCUGAGGAAUGCCAUUGGAUUGCUUGACCACAGCCGGGCUCAGACACAGGUUAUAGCUGAUGACAAAGACAAACUAUGGGGGCUGUGAUGGUGAGCCAGCCUGAAGCUUCUGAGAUGGGAACAAGGUUUAGACAACUGAUGCCUCUAGCUCUAACUUCAUCCCACAUUCCCAGACUAGCUCCCUGUGCUCCAGCCACAUGAUUCAACCAUCUCUAUGUUCUGGACAUACCAAGGCCUUUUUCUCUUGCCUCAGAUCUUAUACCUGCCAUUCUGUUUGUCCAGAAUGCCCAGCAUUUCCUCAUGCCCCUAACCUAGCUAGUUCGUACUCAUCCUUCAAGUCCCCAUUGGGAGUCAGCCUUCUGACUUCCCUCUGAGACUGGGUUAGGUCUCCCGAUAAACACUCAGAGCCCUGCCACUUUCCUUCACAGCAAAUACCACAAUUAUGACUGCACAGUUAUUUUCAUGCUUAUUUUCAAUGGGAAAAUGAAUUAAAGCAGUAUCCUAACAAGGUCACAACUGGAAGGCCAGGCGUGGUGGCUCAUGCCUAUAAUCCUGGCACUUUGGGAGGCCAAGGCAGGCAGAGCACUUGAGGUCAUGAGUUCGAGACCAGCCUAGCCAACAUGGUGAAACCCUGUCUCUACUAAAAAUACAAAAAAUUAGCCGGGUGUGAUGGUGCAUGCCUGUAGUCCCAGCAGGCUGUGGGAGAAUCACUUGAACCUGGAAGGCAGAGGUUGCAGUGAGCUGAGAUUGCACCACUGUACACCAGCCUGGGUGACAGAGUGAGACUCUCUCAAGAAAACAAAACAAAACAAAAAAGGUAACAAUUGGGAAAUGGCUUAAAAUCUAUUCCUUUAAAAACUUUGAUACCUAUCUACACACACACACACACACACACACACACACACACACACACACACACACACGAGGAGGCAGGAAAGUAUACAAAUAUCCUUCAGGUUAAAGGCCAUGAUUUAUUUAUAAUUGAAUGGCUGUAACACCCACCACAACCUACUGGCUAAAUUGAAGAAGGGGUUAACGGGGAAAAAAAAUAAAUUGCCUUCGAUUUUCUCUGUAUGCUAAGAUAAUGAAGUAAAUACACUUGUUCAUAUAGAGCUUAUAGGAACUCCACAUUCUGCAUUUCUGAACAAAUAGAUGGUCAAGGCAGUGCAAGACAAGAUGGAAGAAGCACAAGAUAGGCUGAAGCUGCUCAAGGAACCCAUAAGAACGCCUGUAAUCACUAGGAUUCUAGUGCUUUAAAGGCCAUGGUGGGAGGACUGCUUGAUGAUAAGAGUUCAAGACCAGCCUGGGCAACAUAGCAAGACUCUGUCUCAACAAAAAAAUUUUAAAGUUCGUCUGGCGUUGUGAUCUGCCUGUGGUCCAACUACUCGGGAGGCUGAGGCAGGAAGACUGCUUGAGUCCAAGAGUUUGAGCCUACAGUGAGCUAUGGUUGCACCAGUGCACUCUAGCCUGGGUGACAGAGACUAUGACUCUUAAAAAACAACAAAAAAAGGGGACAUCCAUUAGGGAUAAGAUAAACCUUAGGAGAAAAAAGGUUACAUUUCUUACCUAAUAUAGCAGAUUUUUCCGCGUCAAGCAUAUCCAGAGCCUUGGUGAAAGGCUCUGCCAUUUUGGCUAGCAUUUCUGGUGCAUAUAAUGUAUUGUGGGUUCUGAAAGAAACAAGAAUGCUAUUGAGCUUUUCCAUCUGAUGCAGAAGGAAAGAGUGGGUUUUGCUUGUAAUCCAGUGAUACUACAGUUUCACACAGAUCUGCCCAUCAACUCCUGGCAGGGGAAAGAAAAGAAGGUAUAAAUAUCUGAAUGCUCGCUGGAGGAGGGAACAGACUUGUAUAGAUAUAAUUAUCUUAGUAUACAAUACCUAAGAUAAAUUAACAUGAGAACUAAACCCCAAGACACAGGACAGUAUCAGAGUCCAAAGCUAGAAAGCAAAAUUCUUUUAAAUCUGAGGUGGUCCCAGGAGUUUUUUGACCACCAGUGAUACGGAAUGAAAUGUGUGCAACACUGUGGAUUUACAGGUAGGAACACAGAGGAGGUGGUAAUUUGCCCCAUUUUUCAAUGUUUUGUCUUAAUUCCAAGAGCAUGGACCUUGCAACAGCUGUUUGGACCUGAUAGAGGAACACAAUUCCCAACACAUGCUGUCCCCCACCAAAAUGACCUACCUGAGCAAUUAUAGGCUUUGAGUAAGGAGCAAGGACUGUGAACUUGAUAUACCCGCUGUCCACAGCACUCUUACCUACUCACAGAAAUGACCCCACUGAACAAACUGAUGGCUACACGUUUAAGAUGCAAACUGAAAACAUCUUUUAGACCAUGUUUAAACCUCCAUAGUUUGUUCUUUUUGUUCUUAAGAAGUCAUUCUAGGCUGGGCUCGGUGGCUCACGCCUAUAAUCCCAGUACUUUGGGAGGCCGAGGCUGGCGAAUUACCUGAGGUCAGGAGUUCAAGACCAGCCUGGCCAACAUAGGGAAACCCUGUCUCUACUAAAAAUAUAAAAAUUAGAUGGGUGUGGUGGUGCAUGCGUGUAAUCCCAGUUACUUGGGAGGCUAAGGCAGAAUUGCUUGAACUUGCGAGGCAGAGGUUGUGGUGAGCCGAGAUCAUACCACUGCACUCCAGCCUGGGCAACAGAGUGAGACUCCAUCUCAAAAAAACCCCCCAAAGGCCAGGCGCAGUGGCUCAUGCCUGUAAUCCCAGCACUUUGGGAGGCUGAGGUGGGUGGAUCACGAGGUCAUGAGAUCGAGACUAUCCUGGCUAACACAGUGAAACCCUGUCUCUACUAAAAAUACAAAAAAUUAGCCGGACGUGGUGGUGGGUGCCUGUGGUCCCAGCUACUCGGGAGGCUGAGCUUGCAGUGAGCCAAGACUGCGCCACUGCACUCCAGCCUGGGCAACAGAGCGAGACUCUGUCUCAAAAAACAACAACAACAACAAAACCCCAAAAAACAGAAGUGUUUCUAUGGCUGGGCCCAGUGGCUCACGCUUGUAAUCCCAGCACUUUGGGAGGCCGAGGUGGGUGGAUCAUCUGAGGUCAGGAGUUCAAGACCAGCCUGGCCAACAUGGUAAAACCCAGUCUCUACUAAAAAUAUAAAAAUUAGCCAGGUGUGGUGGUGGGUGCCGGGCAUGGUAGCUACAGGUUUAAGAUGCAAACUGAAAACAUCUUUCAGACCAUGUUUAAGCCUCCAUAGUUUGUUCUGUUUGUUCUUGCUUAAGAAGUCAUUCUAGAGGCCGGGCGCGGUGGAUCACGAGGUCAGGAGAUCGAGACCAUCCUGGGUAACAUGGUGAAACCCCAUCUCUACUAAAAAUACAAAAGCUAAAUUAGCCAGACAUGGUGGCGGGCGCCUGUAGUCCCAGCUACUCGGAAGGCUGAGGUGGGAGAAUGGCGUGAACCCGGGAGGCGGAGCUUGCAAUGAGCUGAAAUCGCGCCACUGCACUCCAGCCUGUGUGACAGAGCGAGACUCCAUCUCAAAAAAAAAAAAAAAAAAGUCAUUCUAGGCCGGGCGCAGUGGCUCACGCCUGUAAUCCCAGCACUUAGGGAGGCCAAGGCCGGAGAAUCACCUGAGGCCAGGAGAUCAAGACCAGCCUGGCCAACAUGGUGAAACCCUGUCUCUACUAAAAAUAUAAAAAUUAGACGAGUAUGGCGGUGCAUGCCUGUAAUCCCAGCUUCUCCGGAGGCUGAGGCAGGAGAAUCACUUGAAUCCAGGUGAGCCAAGAUCGUGCCACUGCACUCCAGCCUGGGUGACAGAGCGAGACUCCCUCUCAAAAAAAAAAGUCAUUCGCUACCCUGGCCAGGCACAGUGACUCAUGCCUGUAAUCCCAGCACUUUGGGAGGCUAAGGCAGACGGAUCACCUGAGGUCAGGAGUUUGAGACCAGCCUGGCCAACAUGGUGAAACCCUGUCUCUACUAAAAAUAUAAAAAUUAGCCGGGUGUGGUGGUGCAUGCCUAUAAUCCCAGCUACUUGAGAGGUCAAGGCAUAAGAAUCGCUUGAACCCAGGAGGCGGAAAUUGCAGUGAGCCGAGAUUGUGCCACUGCACUCCAGCCUGCGCAACACAGUGAGACUCCAACUCGACAAAAAAAAAAAGUCAUUCACUAACCUCAUGCUGUAAAUAUGGUCUAGAAGUUUUACUUUGGCCAGAUGCGGUGGCUUAUGCCUGUAAUCCCAGCACUUUAGGAAGCCGAGGUGGGUGGAUCACGAGGUCAGGAGUUCAAGACCAGUCUCUGGCCAACAUGGUGAAACCCUGUCUCUACUAAGAAUACAGAAAUUAGCCAGGCAUGGUGGCACACGCCUGUAAAUCCCAGCUACUCAGGAGGCUGAGGUAGGAGAAUCGCUUGAACCCGGGAGGCAGAGGUUGCAGUGAGCCAAGGUCGCGCCACUGCACUCCAGCCUGGACGACAGAGUGAGACUCUAUCUAAAAAAAAAAAAAAAAAAAAAAAAAAAAAAAAGCAGCUUUACUUUUUGGGUUUUAAAACACCUGAAAAUUUUUUCUGUGUGUGGUGGCUGGUAGGAAUCUAAUUGUUUUUUCUAACACGGUGAAACAGACAAUAUGGUGUCUGUCCUCGACAACUCAACUCUGCAUAGAAAGCCAACUGUCCCAGCAUUGAAUAAUUGAUUUUUGUUUUGUUUUUUGUUUUUUAAAGAGACAGGGUCUCACUCUACUGCCCAGGCUGGAUUGCAGUGGUGUGUUCAUAGCUCACUGCAGCCUCAAACUCCUGGGCUCAAGUGGCCCUUCCACCUCAGGCUCCCGAGUAGCUGGGACUAUAAGUGUGCACCACCACACGUGAAUAAUUAAAACUUUUUUUUUUUUUUUUGUAGAGAAAGUGUCUGUGUUGCCCAGGCUGGUCUCAAACUCCUGGCCCCAAGAGAUCCUCCUGCCCUGGCCUCCCAAAGUGCUGAAAUUAUAGGCAUGAGCCACUAUUCCCAGCCAUCUUUUUCUAACUUUCAUUACUUCUGUCAUAGAUCAACCUGUAAUACAUACCUGGGAGUCUUUUAAAGGCUAAACCUUUACUAUUGUGUUGAACCCAUCAUCAUCUACAAAGGAUUAUCUGCUAAAAAACUGAACUGGUAUGAGGUCAGUUUUCUAGACCAGAGGUCACAUUCAUACAUGUUUUAAGCUUGGCCGGCAAUAUGGUGUCUGUCCUCGACAACUCAACUCUGCAUUGAAGCGCAAUAGCAGCCAUAAACAGUAGGUAAAUGAAUGGCCAAGGUAUGUUCCAACGGAAGUUUACUUACAAACAUGUGGAGACUUACAUUUGGUCCUCAGGCUGCAGAGUGCCAUAUGUCCUCUAGACAUAUUCACGUGUAACAAAAUAACAAAAAUAAAGGAAAGUAGACAAGAUCAAACAAUACUCCAGAGAUGCAAUCAUCAAAAUUUCACCAGGGGAAACUCUGGAAAUACAAGUCCACAUUUUUCAACAAAUAAAUUGAAAAGAAAAAGAGGGCCAGGCAUGGUAGCUCACGGCUGUAAUCCCAGCACUUUGGGAGGCUGAGGCAGGUGGAUCAGUUGAGCUCAGGAGUUUGAGACCAGCCUGGGUAACAUGGCAAAACCCUGUAUCUACUAAAAAUACAAAAAAUUAGCCAGGCGUGGUGGCGCACACCUGUAAUCCCAGCUACUCGAGAGGCUGAGGCAGUCGAGAGGCUGAGGCAGGAGAAUUGCUUGAUCCCGGGAGGCGGAGGGUGCAGUGAGCUGAGAUAGCACCAGUGCACUCCAGCAUGGGUGACAGAACAAGAUGGUCUCAAAAAAAAAAAAAAAAAAAAGGCAAGGAACUUAUAAAUUUAGAGCCUAAGAGACAUCUUUUUUUUUUUUUUUUUUUUUUUUUUUUGAAACAGAGAUUUGCUCUGUCGCUCAGGCUGGAGUACAAUGGCGUGAUCUCAGCUCAAUGCAACCUCCGCCUGCUGGGUUCAAGUGAUUCUCGUGCCUCAGCCUCCCAAGUAGCUGAGACUACAGGUGCGCACCACCACACCUGGUUACUUUUUUAAAUUUUUAGUAGAGAUGGGGUUUUGUCAUGUUGGCCAGGUUGGUCUCAAACUCUUAGCCUCAAGGAUCCGCCUGCCUCGGCCUCCCAAACUGCUGAGAUCACAAGCGUGAGGCACCACGCUAAGCCUAAUUUAGUGACUAAGAGAUAUCUUAAAUAUAUAUAAACCUUGUGUGGAUAAACAGAAAAAAGGAAAACAUUCGGUGAUAUUUGAAUACUGAUUGUAUACUGGAUAUUGAAUUACUGGUAGUAUUUUGAGAUAUAACAAUGGAAAUGUGGUUAUAUUAAAAGACUUAUUACUAGCUCCAUAUUGCUUUUGAUUUGGGAUUUUCGUCUCUAUGUUUACAAGUGAUUUAGGCCUAUAAUUUUCCUCUUUGGUACUGUUAAUGUCUGGUUUUGGUAUCAAAAUAAAUAAGCCUCAUAAAAUGA